CGCAACCUGACUCCAUUCUCUUCUCCGCUGUGGAAAGUUUGUUCUUUUGCUCUUAGCAAUAAAUCUUGCCGCUCAGUCUGGGUGCGCGCCGCUUUUGUGAGCUGUAGCACUCACCAGGGAGGUCUGCAGCGAAGGUCUGCAGCUUUGCUCUUGAGGCCAGCCAGACCACGAGCCCACCGGAGGGAGCGAACAGCUCCAGACGCGCUGUCUCUGAGAGGCGUAAGUAACACUCACCACUGAGGUCUGAAUUGAAGCCGGCGAGACUAGGAACCCACGGGAAGGAAUGAAUGACUCCAGAGGCGUCACCUUGAAGAGCUGUAACACUCACUGCGAGAGUCCGCGGCUUCACUCCUAAAGUCAGCGAGACCACGAACCCACCAGAAGGAAGAAACUCCAGACGCAUCUGAACAUCUGAAGGAAGAAACUCCAGGGUCGCCAUCUUUAAGAACUGUGACACUCACUGCGGGGCUCCGCAGCUUCAUUCCUGACGUCAGCGAGACCAAUAACCCACCAAUUCCAGACACACUGCGUCCUGUGCUGCAGGGGGAAAGGCACGGACUCAAAACUGCCAGCUUUGUUCUGAUUGGGAGCUCUGCCUGCCUGACAGGCGGCCUGGGCUGAGAAGAGUGGGGCGGUUCACAGGGAGAGUCCCGCGGAGCAGGAGGGCCGUGCGAUGAUAGUGAAAAACAAGAACCAUCUGCCAAAGGGCUGUGCUGCACCCAAAUGGGCUCUGAAAUAAGGAAUGGGACCUGAGCCGCCUUGUUCCUUGGCCCUGUUUAAUGGGGAAGCACCUCCUCGGCAGGAGGGCAGGGCUCCCAGGUCCUAGAAGGCCCCUUGGUGGGACAGGAGGGCUGGGUGAGCUCCACAGGGGCUCUGUCCACUCCUUCCGCUGUGAGGGUGGCUUUUGCUUCUGGGGCUUCGGGUCGCUGUGGUCUUUGAUGUUGCUGUCCCAUUCACCAGCGAGGGUCUCGAGCUGAGAGCUGUCCAGGCUGAAUGCCCAGUGGGCAGUUUGAGGCCAGGAGCACACUGCGUGGGCCCAGCAGGCGCCUUGCAGUGGAGACUUUCCCCUCAGCCCUGCUGGCCAGGGGCCUACCCGGUCUCCCUUGGGGCUGUGCCAUUCCUGUGCUUCGGAUUUACUGGGGGGUUGCUUCUCCCUGGUCCUGAUCCCCUCCACUCCCUCAGUCAGCGACCUGGGUCCAGGUCAUGAUGGAGCACUGGGCGUUGCAGAGGGGCCAUCCCAGGGCUUCGGUGCCAAGGUGGGACCUGUGGCCGUGGGACAUUGGAGGGUCCAUCAGGCCCUCAGGAGCUUUGCCACCUGCAGGCACGAGAGGGUCCCGUUCCAGCAGUGGGGUCUGGCCCUAGGGUUUCCUAAACAGGAGUGGGGUUUAAUGACAACAGUCUCCAGGGACUCUGGGCAGGAUUGAGGGCUGUGAUGGCAGCCAGCCUGGGGUGGAGGGUGCUCCCCCUGGACAGGACUUGGGCGUAAAGGUUCUGAAGAGCCCAGCGGCAGUACACCCAGCUGAGCCUGCGGAGGCCAGGGUAUCUGCAUGGGAAUCUGCCCAUGGAGAGAGGACCAGGGACCCCCAGGGGUUCCUGGCAUGCACUCCCACCUGCAGGGCCUGGGACAGCUCCUGUCACCAGCUGAGAGAUGCCUGAAUACUGCUGAGCGCCUCGGCCCCCACCCCUCCAACCUGUUUCCCAGUCAGCUUGCAACACAGCGUGUCCUUCACAGCUCCCUGGAUGCCAGUGCCCCGAGGGCAUGGAAGGAAGGGGUUGGAGAGAGGCAUCUGAGCCAGCAUGGCCCCUGCCAGGGGCAUCCUGCAGUCACAGCACGUUGGACUCCUGGGCGGCGUCUCCAGGGUUAGAGGGAGCAGCUCCCACCCAGGCCCCAGGCCUCCAAAUCACCAGGGAACCCAUUGUCAUCCCUGAACAGGGAGUUCUCCAGGGCACGAGCAUCGGCUCCUGCCAGGCAGAAGCACGCGGGGCUCCUGGGAACCUGAGUUAACAGAAGGUUUGGGUUGAGUGUGUGGCGUGCGUGCCUGAUGUUCCCAGCCUGGUCCCUUCCCAAGGAAUGCUUGCCUUCGGGUUCUGGUGGAAUCCAGUUGGCUGCCAUCACAGAGUCUUUCUCCGCAGAGACAGGUUCUCCCUCAGGCUGUGCCUGCAUGAGGCCAUCGGGUGCGAGGGAGAUGGGGAGCGGCUGCACCCCUUCAAGGAUGAGGAGACUGAGGCGCAAGCAACUGUCCCACCAUGGGCACCUGCCUGGGAGCGAGCUCUGGGGGUCAGCGGGUGCAGCUGGAGAAGCUGCUGGUGGCUUCUCCAGAGCAGGUGGAGCUGUCAGAGGUCACGCCCUGGCCUGGUCCAGCCCAGCACAACCCAGGGGGCCUGCAGGACACUUGUGACCAGGACAGAGGUUCUCAGGGAGGCCAGAGCCUGAGCAGGGCCGAGGGCUGGCUCUGAGGUCUCAGGUCCCAGGGAGGGGUGAUGAGCUGAGGGGUAGUAGCUCCCACUGACUCCAUGGCUCCUGCCUCCAGCUUUGACCCGGCACUGCUGAUGAUGUGAGCAUGGCCUGUCCACCAGCCUCCUCUGCCAGCAAGGCUCAGCCACCCCACAGCCAUCCACGUGAAGAGCAGUGGUGUAGGCUCUGUCGGCGCCACCCCCGCGUGGGCGUGGGCAGUGAACAAGGGAGCACCGAGGCUGCUGCUAUCUUUAAAACAGCAGCUGGCCCUAGUGAGAGAGACCCCAGGCCCUAGUUACAGGCUCCAGGCCCAAGGGGCAGACCCCUGGCGCUAGUGACAGACCCCAGGUCCUAGUAAUAGGCUCCAGGCCCAAGGGGCAGACCCCUGGCCCUAGUGACAGACCCCAGGUCCUAGUUACAGGCUCCAGGCCCAAGGGGCAGACCCCUAGCCCUAGUGACAGACCCCAGGUCCUAGUAACAGGCUCCAGGCCCAAGGGGCAGACCCCUGGCCCUAGUGACAGACCCCAGGCCGUAGUUACAGGCUCCAGGCUCAAGGGGCAGACCCCUGGCUGUAGUGACAGACCCCAGGUCCUAGUAACAGGCUCCAGGCCCAAGGGACAGGUCCCGGCCCUAGUGACUGACAGGCCCCUGGUCCUAGUGAGAACCCCCUGGCCCAAGUGCGAGACCCCUGUUCCUAGUGACAGAGCCCGGUCAGUCCUAGUGCCUGGCCCCGCUUACUGAUGCCACAUGGACACCCGGGUUUCCAGCCCCUGGACAGCUCUGUGAUCAGAGGCUGGGGCUGCUGUUUCCCCAGCCCUGUCAAUUCUGUUCUGGCAGGUUUUCUGUAAGUUUGGCUUUGGGCAGUCCAGUGUCCAGUCUGAAGGCAUUUCCCAGGAGAUUCAUUCUGACAAAUGGGGCCCAGCAACAUGGCUGACAAGGCCAAGCCUGCCAAAGCUGCCAACAGGACGCCCCCCAAGUCCCCGGGGGACCCCUCGAAGGACUGGGCAGCCAAGAAGCUGUCGCUGGAGUUGGAGGACAUGUGCACCGAGUGGUGUGGACGGCCGUCUCGCGGGGCUGUGGUGCUGGUCAGACCUCGAGGAGGAGACCCACCCGGUGGACUUGAGCUCGCUCUCCAGUAAGCUACUCCCAGGCUUCACCACGCUGGGCUUCAAAGACGAGAGAAGAAACAAAGUCACCUUUCUCUCCAGUGCCACUACUGCGCUUUCGAUGCAGAAUAAUUCAGCAUUUGGCGACUUGAAGUCGGACGAGUUGGAGCUGCUCUACUCAGCCUACGGAGAUGAGACAGGCGUGCAGUGUGCGCCGAGAUGGACACCCGCUCCGGGAGCCAGUGUUCCGUCACCCCAGAAGCCAUACGCAACAAUGAAGAGCUGGUCUUGCCGCCCCGCAUCUCCAGAGUGAACGGCUGGUCGUUACCCCUGCACUACUUCCGGGUGGUGACUUGGGCUGUCUUCGUUGGCCUUUCCUUGGCCACCUUCAGGAUCUUCAUUCCCCUCCUGCCUCACUCGUGGAAAUACAUCGCCUAUGUGGUGACCGGGGGGAUCUUCUCGUUCCACCUCGUCGUCCACCUGAUCGCGUCCUGCAUCGACCCGGCCGACUCCAAUGUCAGACUCAUGAAGAACUAUUCUCAGCCCAUGCCCCUCUUCGACAGAUCAAAACAUGCACACGUGAUCCAGAAUCAGUUCUGCCACCUGUGCAAGGUCACCGUGCCUCAACACCCUCCCCCAGCCUCCCAUUCCCUGCUGGACGCCCUCUCCCCAGGCCGCACAGGGCUGGUUCCUCCGAGGCACCUGGCUUCCAGUGAUGGACCUCUGGCCCUGCCCCAACCUGCGCACUUGGGGCCUGACAGGCGUUCCCCGAUUCAUCCCUCCAGGAACAAGAAAACCAAACACUGCAUUUCCUGCAAUAAGUGUGUGUCCGGCUUCGACCACCACUGCAAAUGGAUCAACAACUGCGUGGGAAGCCGGAAUUAUUGGUUCUUCUUCAGCACUGUGGCCUCGGCCACAGCUGGCAUGCUCUGCCUGAUCGCCAUCCUGCUGUAUGUCCUCGUCCAGUACCUCGUGAACCCCAGGGUGCUCCGCACGGACCCCAGGUAUGAAGAUGUCAAGAAUAUGAACACGUGGCUGCUGUUCCUCCCCCUGUUCCCGGUGCAGGUGCAGACUCUGAUAGUCGUGAUCAUCAGGAUGCUCGUGCUCCUGCUGGACCUUCUUGGCUUGGUGCAGCUGGGCCAGCUGCUCAUCUUCCACAUCUACCUGAAGGCCAAGAAGAUGACCACCUUUGAGUAUCUCAUUAAUACCCGCAAAGAAGAGAGUUCAAAACAUCAAGCAGUGAGGAAAGAUCCAUACGUGCAAAUGGACAAAGGAUUUCUCCAGCAAGGAGCUGGCGCCCUGGGCUCAUCUGCACAGGGAGUCAAGGCCAAGAGCUCCCUGCUGAUUUACAAAUGCCCAUGUCACUUCUGCACUUCAGUAAACCAGGACGGGGAUUCGAAGGCACAGGAAAAGACCAGCGCGGCUGCCGGCUUUAGGGCCACAUAUUUCUGUUCCUGCUCUGGGGUCAGCUUCCAGUGGUUUCUGCUGGGUCAUUAUUUAUUUUUUAGAGAUGAGAUCUCACUCCAUCACCCAACAUGGAUGGCAGUGGUGGGAUAAUGGCUCACUGCAGCCUCCAACUCCUGGGCUCAAGCAAUUGUCCCACCUCAGCCUCCCGAAUAGCCGAAAGUACAGGUGUGUGCCACCACACCCAGCCAAUUUAUUUUUUGUUUUUUAUUUCUUAAGAGAUGGGAUCUCACUCUCUUGUCCAGGCUUGUUUGGAACUUCUGGUCUCAAGUGAUUCCCCAGGCUCAGGGGAAUUAGAGGCGUGAGCCUCUAAUAGCACAGGGAUUAGAGGCGUGAGCCUCCAUGCCAGGCCACAGGCUGGUCCUUUUGAGCAGGAUUUGUGAGGGGGCCAGUUUCUGGAGGUUACAGGUGACUUGUCCUUCCCUGUGGGGGCAGGGCCGCCUCACCGCACUUCCCCAGGAUUUCAGGGAACAGGCUCCUGUGACUUGGAAAUGAAAAUGGAUCACCCAACCUGGAGGAACAGUGAGGCUGGUGUCCAAGACUUGCCCCUUGCCUGCACUUCCAGCAAAGAUUUGGAGACACUCAGUGGAAACCAAUCGAGCCCCCAGCCCACCCCCGCCCAGACUCAGCCACCAAAGUUCCCUCACUGCAUGUGGCACACGGGCUCAUGGGAGUUUCUCUGCCUGCGAUUGUCCACGUUGACACCUUCUGCACAGGUGCAUUUGUGAGUCCCCUCGGUGUCUCUGCAGCAUCUAUGUGUGGAUGAAUAGUGAAGCCACAUGAGGCCUGGUCUGAAGCAGAGAAGAUCCGCUCAGCAUCACGUUGAAUCCCAAGCCCGCAUCUCCGUGGGCUCCAGGACAAUCCUAUGAAAAUGACACCGUCGGUUCAUUGUUCACAUCGGGGAGGAGAAUUCCGUCUGAAAAUGAGCGUGACUUCACUGACACCCAAGUCCGUGGCACAGCCCUGUGCUGAGCUCCACAGACCUACAGUCCAUCGCCUCCCCUUCGAGUGGGCCCAGGGCUGCAGACAGCAUUGUCCAAAGAAGACACCCUGACUCGAUGAAUGGAACAAACUGGAAACUCCAGAAACAAGCCCUUCUUUACAUUUCUGGUGUUUGGCCUAAAUGGAAGGUGCCAAGGAAGCAGAUGAUGCCCCGAGUACAUCUACACUUGGGCUGCAACAAGAAACAACAGAGCCCAUGAAAACUGACAGUGCUGAAAGUGAAGACUGAGAUUCGGGAGCUCAGGUGCCCCUGUGAUCCAGGUCUUCUACCCUGAAACCCCACCCUCCAUCAAGGUCCUGCCUGUAGAGUCUACCUUGCAAAGCCUCCUGCUCCUACCCAUGCUACAGGCCAGGAACCAGAGCCCAUCAUCUCAGAGGCCCCUGGAUGUCCUUCGAAGGAACCAGGACCCUCAGAGCCCAGCAUCCAUCUCUGUCAUCAUCUUCAUCACACCCAAAGAAGAGCCAGCCUUGCAGGAGGGUUUACAUCUCCAGGAAGAUGGGCUGCCAGCAACUGCAGAGGAUGCAGCCACCUGCUUAACUGUGCUGUCCAGCCAGCCAGCCAGCUGCAGGGCCUCUUGCUGCUUAAGAGCUGAUGGGCCGGGCAUGUUGGCUCACACCUGUGAGCACAGUACUGGGAAAUGGGAGCAUAGUACUGGGAAAUGGGAGCACAGUACUGAGAAAUGGGAGCACAGUACUGGGAAAUGGUAGCACAGUACUAGGAAAUGGGAUCACAGUGCUGGGAAAUGGGAGCACAGUAAUGGGAAAUGGGAGCACAGUGCUGGGAAAUGGGAGCACAAAGUACUGGGAAAUGGGAGCACAGAGUACUGGGGAAUAGGAGCACAGUACUGGGAAAUGGGAGCAAACAGCACUGGGAGAUAGGAGUAUACAGCACUGGGAAAUGGGAGCACGGCACUGGGAAAUGGGAGCACAGUACUGGGAAAUGGGAGCACAGUGCUAGGAAAUGAGAGCACAGUUUUGGGAAAUGGGAGCACAGUACUGGGAAAUAUGAGCACAGUACUGGGAAAUGGAAGCACAUGGCACUGGGAAAUAGGAGUAUACAGCACUGGGAAAUGGGAGCACAGUACUGGGAAUUGGGAGCACAGCACUGGGAAAUGGGAGCACAGUACUAGGAAAUGGGAGCUCACAGCACUGGGAAAUGGGAACAUAGUACUGGGAAAUGGGAGCACAGUACUGGGAAAGGGGAGCCCACAGUACUGGGAAUUGGGAGCACAGUACUGGGAAAUGGGAGUUCACAGCACUAGGAAAUGGGAGCACAGUAUUGGGAAAUGGGAGCACAGUACUGGGAAAGGGGAGGGCACAGCACUGGGAAAUGGGAGCAUAGUACUGGGAAAGCGGAGCACAGUACUGGGAAAGGGGAGCCCAUAGUACUGGGAAAUGGGAGCACAGUACUGGAAAAUGGGAGCUCACAGCACUGGGAAAUGGGAGCAUAGCAUUGGGAAAUGGGAGCACAGUACUGGGAAUUGGGAGCACAGCGCUGAGAAAUGGGAGCUCACAGUACUGGGAAAUGGAGCACAGUAUUUGGAAAUGGGAGCACAGUACUGGGAAAUGGGAGCUCACAGCACUGGGAAAUGGGAGCAUAGCAUUGGGAAAUGGGAGCACAGUACUGGGAAUUGGGAGCACAGUACUGGGAAAUGGGAGCUCACAGUACUGGGAAAUGGGAGCUCACAGUACUGGGAAAUGGGAGCACAGUAUUCGGAAAUGGGAGCACAGUACUGGGAAAUGGGAGCUCACAGCACUGGGAAAUGGAGCAUAGCAUUGGGAAAUGGGAGCACAGUACUGGGAAAUGGAAGCUCACAGUCCUGGGAAAUGGGAGCAUAGUGCUGGGAAAUGGGAGCACAGUACUGAGAAAUGGGAGCACAGUACUGGGAAAUGGGAGCCCAGUACUGAGAAAUGGGAGCACACAGUACUGUGAAAUGGGAGCACAGUACUGGGAAAUGGGAGCAUAGUACUGAGAAACCCCAGACCUGGAUUCUGAGUUUUUCAGUCUAGCCCAGACUUCUUAUCUUAGUAGACAAAAAGAGUCAAUACCAGAGAACCAGAGGCAUCCUCUGUAUUUUAAUGAACUCUGCGUUUUAGUCUGUUUAGUAGUCAUAUUUUAAAAGAUAAUCAGUUUUCUAAAUAUAUCUAUAAGUUACUACAUGCA